AUUACAAAAGAGCUAGGGUCCUAGAUUGUGCCGAAGCUUCAUGAGACCUCUCCUCGUCUGUGCACGGACGAGUGGCCGACUCUGGAGCCCAGGCUGUUGUUUCCUAGUCUGGUGGUGAAUCCGCCAUAGUCUGGUGAGUGCAGUGUCCGACUCUCGAGCCCAGGCUGUUGCUGUUGCUUCCCAGUCUGGUGGUGAAUCCUCCAUAGUCUGGGACAAAUAUGGCCCUGAAGGCUCCAUGAGCAGACGAGAAGGCUGGACUUCGCAACUGGGUCACCUUAGAUCCGGAACUAGAGAAUGACACCGUUGUUUCCGGGAGGAAAAAGAAAAAGCGCUUGACCCGGAAGCUGCGUGUCCCAUCCCCGCGCCUGCUUCUCUGACUGGGGAAGCCCGACAUCCCAGUGCCUUACCUGUAUUUCGACAUGGGGGCAGCCGUGCUGUGCGCUAGUUUCAUGUCCUUUGGCGUGAAGCGGCGCUGGUUCGCGCUGGGGGCCGCACUCCAAUUGGCCAUUAGCACCUACGCCGCCUACAUCGGGGGCUACGUCCACUACGGGGACUGGCUGAAGGUCCGUAUGUACUCGCGCACAGUUGCCAUCAUCGGCGGCUUUCUUGUGUUGGCCAGCGGUGCUGGGGAGCUGUACCGCCGGAAACCUCGCAGCCGCUCCCUGCAGUCCACCGGCCAGGUGUUCCUGGGUAUCUACCUCAUCUGUGUGGCCUACUCACUGCAGCACAGCAAGGAGGACCGGCUGGCGUAUCUGAACCAUCUCCCAGGAGGGGAGCUGAUGAUCCAGCUGUUCUUCGUGCUGUAUGGCAUCCUGGCCCUGGCCUUUCUGUCAGGCUACUACGUGACCCUCGCUGCCCAGAUCCUGGCUGUACUGCUGCCCCCUGUCAUGCUGCUCAUUGAUGGCAAUGUUGCUUACUGGCACAACACGCGGCGUGUUGAGUUCUGGAACCAGAUGAAGCUCCUUGGAGAGAGUGUGGGCAUCUUCGGAACUGCUGUCAUCCUGGCCACUGAUGGCUGAGUUUUAUGGCAAGAGGCUGAGAUGGGCACAGGGAGCCACUGAGGGUCACCCUGCCUUCCUCCUUGCUGGCCCAGCUGCUGUUUAUUUAUGCUUUUUGGUCUGUUUGUUUGAUCUUUUGCUUUUUUAAAAUUGUUUUUUGCAGUUAAGAGGCAGCUCAUUUGUCCAAAUUUCUGGGCUCAGCGCUUGGGAGGGCAGGAGCCCUGGCACUAAUGCUGUACAGGUUUUUUUCCUGUUAGGAGAGCUGAGGCCAGCUGCCCACUGAGUCUCCUGUCCCUGAGAAGGGAGUAUGGCAGGGCUGGGAUGCGGCUACUGAGAGUGGGAGAGUGGGAGACAGAGGAAGGAAGAUGGAGAUUGGAAGUGAGCAAAUGUGAAAAAUUCCUCUUUGAACCUGGCAGAUGCAGCUAGGCUCUGCAGUGCUGUUUGGAGACUGUGAGAGGGAGUGCGUGUGUUGACACAUGUGGAUCAGGCCCAGGAAGGGCACAGGGGCUGAGCACUACAGAAGUCACAUGGGUUCUCAGGGUAUGCCAGGGGCAGAAACAGUACCGGCUCUCUGUCACUCACCUUGAGAGUAGAGCAGACCCUGUUCUGCUCUGGGCUGUGAAGGGGUGGAGCAGGCAGUGGCCAGCUUUGCCCUUCCUGCUGUCUCUGUUUCUAGCUCCAUGGUUGGCCUGGUGGGGGUGGAGUUCCCUCCCAAACACCAGACCACACAGUCCUCCAAAAAUAAACAUUUUAUAUAGACA